CUCUGCCAGCCCUGAGCUGGGAAGAAGCAGCUACCUCGGAGGCAGGGCGCGCAGGCGGGCGGCGAUGAGAGGGGGCGCAGCCGCAGCCCCGCGCUGGGGAGCCCACCGCUAACCCUGCACCCCACCCACCCCUGCACAAAAGAGCUGGCGGGCGCUGGCCACGUCGCCCUGGGUGACCUUCCUCGGAUGCAGAAUCCGCCCCUGCGAGCAUCCUCUUCCUCCUAGGCUCUGAAGGCCCGGGGAGCGUGAGCGAUGCCCAGCUGCACCCGGGCAGGGCUCGCCUUUGUUUGCCAGUAAGGAGGAGAGGCUGUCUCAGCUGCAGAGGGGUCAUCCCUGCUUCAAGCCAGUGCCUCUUCCCAGCUCCCAUGGGGACCACCGAAGCCACGCUCCGGAUGGAAAACGUGGACGUGAAGGAGGAAUGGCAGGACGAAGAUCUUCCCAGGCCACUCCCAGAAGAGACGGGGGUGGAACUGCUUGGCAGCCCGGUGGAAGACACAUCCUCUCCUCCCAACACGCUAAAUUUCAACGGAGCGCAUCGUAAGAGGAAGACGCUGGUGGCCCCAGAGAUCAACAUUUCUCUGGAUCAGAGUGAGGGGUCCCUGCUGUCCGAUGACUUCUUGGAUACCCCUGAUGACCUGGAUAUUAACGUGGAUGACAUCGAGACCCCCGAUGAGACCGACUCGCUGGAGUUCCUGGGGAAUGGCAACGAACUGGAGUGGGAAGACGACACCCCCGUGGCCACCGCCAAGAACAUGCCCGGGGACAGCGCGGAUCUAUUUGGGGACGGCACGACGGAGGACGGCAGCGCCGCCAACGGGCGCCUGUGGCGGACAGUGAUCAUCGGGGAGCAAGAGCACCGUAUAGACCUGCACAUGAUCCGGCCUUACAUGAAAGUGGUCACCCACGGAGGGUACUACGGCGAAGGCCUCAACGCCAUCAUCGUCUUCGCAGCCUGCUUCCUUCCAGACAGCAGCCUCCCCGACUACCACUACAUCAUGGAGAACCUCUUCCUGUACGUCAUCAGCAGCUUAGAGCUCCUGGUGGCUGAGGACUACAUGAUCGUGUACCUGAACGGUGCCACGCCCCGGCGGAGGAUGCCUGGAAUCGGCUGGCUGAAGAAGUGCUACCAGAUGAUCGACCGGAGGUUGCGGAAAAACCUGAAGUCCUUGAUCAUCGUCCACCCCUCGUGGUUCAUUCGGACUGUGCUGGCCAUCUCUCGCCCUUUCAUCAGCGUCAAGUUCAUCAACAAGAUCCAGUACGUGCACAGCUUGGAAGACCUGGAGCAACUCAUCCCUAUGGAACACGUCCAGAUCCCAGACUGCGUCCUGCAAUACGAAGAGGAAAGACUGAAGGCCAGGAGGGAGAGCGCGAGGCCCCAGCCGGAGUUUGUGCUGCCCAGGUCUGAAGAGAAGCCAGAGGUGGCACCAGUGGAAAACAGGUCUGCUCUGGUCUCAGAAGAUCAGGAAACAAGCAUGUCCUGAGGCGACGUGAGCAUAACAAAGGACAUGGAAGAAGAUUCCAGAUGCCAGAAAACCUCUGUCAGACGCCCACUGGCCCCAGAUCUCAUCCUGCCUCAUCCUGAGUCCCAAUCUUCCAAGGGUGCCAGCCCCUCCGUUCAUCUCUGAAACCCAGCAUCCUUUUCAGCUGCUUGAAAACAUUGUAUUUUUUUUUUUUAACGAUGCAGUAUUUGUGCGUUCCAGAAAAGGGCCCAGCUCUGAGCCCCUCACCCUUCCACACUCACGAACUCUCAGCCGAGGAAGGCAAGAAGCGCAGGGGGUGGCCCGCGUGGCGUCGGUGGCCUCCGCUCCUGCUCGCAGCCUCUGUGGUCAGAGCUGGAUACAAGAUUCAAGACCCUUCUCUUGCUUGUCACCCGCUCCAGGUUGGAGCCACAGACACCCACCGCCACCCCGGCUGGGUCUGCGUCCUUUCCUGUGCCUUUCCCUCCAGAAUGCGGCCUCAGACCUAGAAGCUCAACCCCCCUAUGAGGGCCACGUCCUGGGGUAGCUCCUGACCUCCGACCUUAUGUCCAAAUUUCACACCCAUGGUUUUUCAUUUGACCCGCCCCCUUCUCGCUCAUAAUGACACCCAGCUCCUUUGAGAGGAUCAGAGCCCAUUGCACAAGAAGAGCCGCUGCCAACCAUCCUUGUCCUCCGAUUGCAAAAUGACACCCCAGUAAUCUAGAACAUUCUCAAGCCCCUUUAACUCAGAUGUCAAGCCACCGGGCAAACCCCGUCAAUACCUCCCACCAAGGAAUGAGAUAUGUGGACCUCACUGCUCCCCCAACCCAGCGUCAGGCUGGGACACGCCAACGCUGUUCCGGGUUGGAACAGCAGAGGCUCAGAAACUGGCUCUGAAAUAGGCAGACCUAGCAAGAGGAAGAUACAGGGUAUCGGGCGUUUGAGUGUUUCAGAAGUCAUUCGGGAAGAUAAAUCCAGUGCGCUGGCCGCAGCCACCUGCAUUCAAAGCUUGGACCAGCGGGUUCUUGUUCGGGAGGCAAAUUUCCCUAGGAAAAAGAAGACAGACUUUUCUAAUGUGGUCCAAAUGCGGAUCACUGGUCAGAUGGACUCUAGAAGCACUGAGCUCCCUGUCUCUGGAAGUAUUUAAGAAAAGGCUGGGCCAGGCACGAUGGCUCACGCCUGUAAUCCCAGACUUUGGGAGGCCGAGGCAGGCGGAUCACCUGAGGUGAGGAGUUUGAGAACAGCCUGGCCAACAUGGUGAAACCUCAUCUCUACUAAAAAUACAAAAAUUAGCCAGGCGUGGUGGCAGGUGCCUGUAAUCCCAGCUACUUGGGAGGCUGAGGCAUGAGAAUCACUUAAACCUGAGAGGCAGAGGUUACAGUGAGCCAAGAUCGUGCCACUGCAUUCCAGCCUGGGCGACAGAGCAAGACUCUGUCUCAAAAAAAAUAAAAAAUAAUCAGGGCACAGUGGCUCAUGCCUGUAAUCCCAGCACUCUGGGAGGCUGAGGUGGGUGGAUCACCUGAGGUCAGGAGUUCAAGACCAGCCUGGUGAACAUGGCGAAACCCCGUCUCUAAUAAAAAUACAAAAAUUAGCCGGGCAUGGUGGUGCAUGCCUGUAAUCCCAGCUACUCGGGAGGCUGAGGCAGGAGAACUGCUUGAACCCAGGAGGCAGAGGUUGCAGUGAUCCAAGAUCAUGCCACUGCACUCCAGCCUGGGCAACAAGAGCAAAACUCCGUCUCAAAAUAAAAAGAAAAGAAAAGAAUGGACAGUGUUUGCAGAGAGUUGCUCACGAGUUUCCCUCUAAUCCUAAAUGUCUUCAUGUCUAUCAGUCUGAGCAGACGGUGAGUAGGGCGGGCACAUUCUCCAGGCCCUUCUUCCUAGCUCUGUGGUUGACCUCUCAGCAAGUGCUAUCCAGGCUGGGCCAACCAGACCCACAAUUAACUGAGCCUCAGUGAAAGCGUCCAGUGCAUCUUGACCUGAGACAGCAAGGAAUUGCAUUUGGGGUUAUUCCAACGAUGAUGGCAGGGAACUGGUGGUAUUUAGUGCUGAGGGGCAGUGAUACAGAAAGAUUUGCCCUGUGGGACAGGGUCCUGCGCGAGUCCCAUCCCCAAAAGCCAGCAGCUCCUGCCAUGAGGAAGACGGGGUUUCUGAGCAGGCUUAUGCCUGCAGGUUCCUGUGGAGCCACCGGCUGUGACGGGACACCUCUGGGUCUCAGCAUUGCCCUGGGGAGGCUGGGACAUUUAGGGACAUGGUAGGGUUUUAACAUUUGUUUCCCAAAUGUCAAAUCCCGGGCACAGGGGCAAGACCCUGUCCCGAAUUCCCACCCCAGUGAAUGGUGUCGCUGCCAAAGCCAACACAAGAUGACAAAAGUGGCUGGGUACGGUGGCUCACGCCUAUAAUCCCAGCACUUUGGGAGACCGAGACAGGUGGAUCACCUGAGGUCAGGAGUUCGAGACCAGGCUGGCCAACAUGGUGAAACCCCAUCUCUACUAAAAAUACAAAAAUUAGCUGGGUGUGGUGGCGCGCACCUGUAGUCCCAGCUACUCAGGAGGCUGAGGUAGAAGAAUAGCUGGAACCCAGGAGGCAGAGAUUGCAGUCAGCCGAGAUUGCACCACUGCACUCCAGCCUGGGAGACAGAGCAAGACUGACUCAAAAGAAAAAAAAUGACAGAAGCCUGAUUAUCAGACUGCCCGGAGGAGACAGGCUCCAGCAGAUAGAUGCCAGCCAGGCCCAGCUGCCACGAUUUGUCCCAGGUGACCAAAGGCACGCAGCUCCAGCAUGAAUCGUUCUAACCCAACAGUGACAAGAACUGCUGGGCCUUAACCGUCAUGGAAGACUGGGGCCGCUUCCAAGUCACAGACAGGAGACGGGGACAGGAAAGAACUCAUUCCACCCAAUCGGACACCUAAUAAUUGAGUGUCUACAGCAGCAAUCAAGUGACAAGUGAGGCCCUACCUGACCCAGAAGGUGCCUGCCGGCUAAACAUUCUGCCCCCACCAGAAACUCCAGGGGGUCCGCCCGUUAUGCCGUGGCCCACCCACGCCCCUUUGGAUCACCAGCAGUCACAGACAACAGGCAGGCGAAACUGAAGACCCCAACUCAGCCCCAGCGGACCCUCCAGAGCAAAAGAGGCCCCCGGCGAGGCCACCUGUCGGCAGGCAUGCCGAGGUCAAACAGCCGGGGCCACCGUUCCCAGCUGGGCCACGACCUGCACCGUCCACAGAUGGGCUUUGAGAUGGAUUUGUAUCAGGGUGGGGGGUGUGGUUUGGCCAAAAUGCAAUGGACCCCGACCCCUCCUCGUAAAAGGAUGUUGGGUUUCCCUCUGGUGACACAUGGGAUGCGUCAUAAACCCUCCCCCAAAGUCCUGGUCAGCAGCCCAUCCUUCCAACGAUGAGUUUUGCGGUUUUUCAGAACAGAAAUGAUCACUACGAUUGACGACGGUCGUGAUGUUAAGACGUCGUCUCCAUGAGCUUUGGGGGGACUUUUAUGUGGAAUAAAGAAACUAUCACUGAGAA